CCCUUUCCCCUGGCUGGCAGCGCGGAGGCCGCACGGUAAGCGGGGGCUCCGAGCUGGACCGGGCGCGAGGCGGCAGGGCCGGACGCCGAAGCCUCAGAGCGCGUGCCUGAGGGCCCCGAGGCGCCCGGCGCGGGCCCGUCCCGCCCCCUAGAGCCGCGGCCACGUGCGAGCGGCAGGCCCGGACAUGCCCGAUGCCUGGAGUUACUGUAAAAGACGUGAACCAGCAGGAGUUCGUCAGAGCUCUGGCAGCCUUCCUCAAAAAGUCCGGGAAGCUGAAAGUCCCCGAAUGGGUGGAUACCGUCAAGCUGGCCAAGCACAAAGAGCUUGCUCCCUACGAUGAGAACUGGUUCUACACGCGAGCUGCUUCCACAGCGCGGCACCUGUACCUCCGGGGUGGCGCUGGGGUUGGCUCCAUGACCAAGAUCUAUGGGGGACGUCAGAGAAACGGCGUCAUGCCCAGCCACUUCAGCCGAGGCUCCAAGAGUGUGGCCCGCCGGGUCCUCCAAGCCCUGGAGGGGCUGAAAAUGGUGGAAAAGGACCAAGAUGGCGGCCGCAAACUGACACCUCAGGGACAAAGAGAUCUGGACAGAAUCGCCGGACAGGUGGCAGCUGCCAACAAGAAGCAUUAGAACAAACCAUGCUGGGUUAAUAAAUUGCCUCAUUCGUAAUCCUGGUCUGGGUCUCUUUUUUGAGUCUCUUGCUCUGUCGCCCAGGCUGGAGUGCAGUGGCGCCAUCUCAGCUCACUGCAAUCUCCGCCUUCUGGGUUCAAAUGAUUCUCCUGCCUCAGCCUCCCAAAGUGCUGGGAUUACAAGUGUGAGCCACUGUGCCUGGUCUGGUUUGGGUCUCUUGAUUGUUCUUCAGGGGCAUGAGGAAGAGGCGCUUCCUCCCUUCCCUUGGGUGAGGGGGCCCAGGGUGAUUGGGUGGCUGUUUACCCGGCAGCCAGUCGGGCCUUCCCAGGUCAAACAGUUCCCAUCUGGGUUUGGAGGAAGGACCCAGGGGCCCUUGUGGCUCACUCCCCCACAUCCUGUCUUUGCAAUUGUCAGAAAGUGAGAAACGAAAGGAUGGCUGUGAGCUGUGACCUCAGCUGGGCCUGGGCUGCAGAGGUGGCUUCCGCUGGAGUAAAGCAAGAGGGCCCAGGGUUCAUGCUCUUCCCUGGAAGGUAGAAAAGGACAGACCACCAGGGAGCCUCCACCGCAAACUGACCUGUGCUGCCUACACACUAACUUUCCUGGGCCUGGGGCCUGCACAGGCUGAAUGGUCCUUGAGCCUUCACUCUGCAUCUGAGCGGUCUUGGGCCCGCUGAGUGGCAGUGGCAGGAAGUCGGUGGAAGCAGAUCCCUGUGCAGAAGUUGAAUUACCAGGGCGGCCACACACGGGCUGCACAACCUUUGCAGUCGUGCACGGCAAGUGGGAUGUGGCCUCCGCCCAUGAUUGGGCACCUGGUCAGGCUGGGAGAUCCAAAUAGCACCCAGUGGGCAGCUGUCCGACCCCUGGAGGGGCAAGCCAGGAAAGAAACUUAGGGCCCGCUGUGACCAGAUGUCCCUCCCAGUUGGGAAGACUAAACUGGUUUGGCCAAUAUCUCCCAGGAUUCCCCUGUCCAAAUUAUUCCUGGGAUCUGACCCAUUUCCUGGAAAGGGGCGAGCCUGGGUUUUGAAGUUCAAACUAGAGUUUAAAUCACAACUCUGCCCCUAAUCCCACGUAACCCUGUGCACCUUAUCCUCUGAGCCUUCGUCUCCUCGUGUGUAAGCCUGCUAACUCCUGAGAGACUGGACAAGAUGCCGUGGAGAGCCUUGGCUCUGAGUAGCUCUGCUGCUGGACAGUUCAGUUGGCAGUCCCCAAACGUAAGGCGUAAGAGUUUAAGAAGUAUCGGCCAGGCACAGUGGCUCACACCUGUAAUCUCAACACUUUGGGAGGCCGAGACGGGCUGAUCACCUGAGGUUGGGAGCUUGAGAACAGCCUGACCAACAUGGAGAAACCCUGUCUCUAAAAAUACCAAAAUUAGUUGGGCAUGGUGGCGCGCACCUGUAAUCCCAGCUACUCAGGAGGCUGAGGCAGAAGAAUCGCUCGAACCCCGGAGGCGGAGGUUGCAGUGGGUUGAGAUCGAGCAAUUGCAAUCCAGCCUGGGCAACAGAGCGAGACUCCAUUUCAAAAAAAGAAUCAAUAAAAAUGUUAAAAGCA